GGAAGUGCUCCCCCGGCGCGGUCCGCCAGGCCAGUGCCCUCAGGUAGGCGGGGCCCCUGGCCCUAAACUCUGGGACUGGCGGGCGGUCAGGCGGCACAGGGGGAAUCCCGGGGGCCUAAGGAGGUUGUCCCAGUUUUUGUCAGCAUCUCCACCCCGAGGUGGUUUGAACUUUGAGCCUUUUGUAGUCCUGAUGAAUAAUUUCAUUUUCCUCAAGUUUAUGACACUCGGAACGUCAAGAACUGGAGGUUUGUGCAAUUUGAGACCGGUCGGCACUGUGCAGAGAUCAGAGUACUAAGAGACAGAGAUUAAAAUGGCUUCCAGAGGAAAGACAGAGACAAGCAAAUUAAAGCAGAAUUUAGAAGAACAGUUGGAUAGACUCAUGCAACAAUUACAAGAUCUGGAGGAAUGCAGAGAGGAACUUGAUACAGAUGAAUAUGAAGAAACCAAAAAGGAAACUCUGGAGCAACUAAGUGAAUUUAAUGAUUCACUAAAGAAAAUUAUGUCUGGAAAUAUGACUUUGGUAGAUGAACUAAGUGGAAUGCAGCUGGCUAUUCAGGCAGCUAUCAGCCAGGCCUUUAAAACCCCAGAGGUCAUCAGAUUGUUUGCAAAGAAACAACCAGGUCAGCUUCGGACAAGGUUAGCAGAGAUGGAUAGAGAUCUGAUGGUAGGAAAGCUGGAAAGAGACCUGUACACUCAACAGAAAGUGGAGAUACUAACAGCUCUUAGGAAACUUGGAGAGAAGCUGACUGCAGAUGAUGAGGCCUUCUUGUCAGCAAAUGCAGGUGCUAUACUCAGCCAGUUUGAGAAAGUCUCUACAGACCUUGGCUCUGGAGACAAAAUUCUUGCUCUGGCAAGUUUUGAGGUUGAAAAAACAAAAAAAUGACAUGGUGCAGAAGCUUGUAACAUUGAUCACAUUCUUAAUGUAAAUGGUGUCUUUCUUCUGGGGUUUUCAGUUAUUGCAAAGAAAUGAAGAGAUUCUGGAAAUGCAUCAAUAACCUAAGAAAAAGCGACAUAAAAAUAUACUUAUGGCUUGUGUUUAUGCUCUUCAUCAUUGUGCGUUGUGUGCGGUUACCUGCUUGAGUGAUCCUGAACUUGUUGCGACAGAGGGACUCACUGGACUCUGUUCGUUAUGAUUUGUCUGUUUAAGAGAGAAAACAAAGUGGACUUGAUUUUUAUUAAGGCUGUUUGUUUUUAAGUGUUGAUAGUGAACGAAAAGAUGUGAAGUAAUGAUAUUUUUCUGCUUACAACUUAUCCCCACUCAUUGGAGUGAACAGUGACGCAAGCUCAAUAGACUUCAUAAGUGUUCAUAGAAUUUUACAAUUCUGAGUGAUCUUAGAAAUCAUUUCUGUUUUUACAAACAAGGAAACUGAGGUCCAGAAAGAGCAAGCGACUUUGCUUAAAGUCGCAUCAGAGAGCUGAGGGUAAGACUCAGGUGUCCUGACUCCCAGUUUAGUAUCUUUUGAAUUUUAUUUCUGUACCAUUUAAAAAAAAUAAUUAACACUAUUUGUGCAAGUCAGUGUUUUUGAAAAUUCAGUGUCCCAAUAAAAAGUGGACUGCACACUAAGGGACCAUCCCCCAGCCUGUAAGCUGUCUGUAUUAAUGGGGCCCGUUGUAUCUCGGAAUUUUGAGGUUGGAACAAUGGGAGCCCUGUUGAGCGUUUCCUAAAGUGACUUAGCCGCCUGCGUUGUUUGACCAGGGAAGCAACAGGAAAUGGCAGCUAGAGGCCCUCCCUGUGCGUGACCUCUUGUCACACUCAGAGGGGGGUAACUGUCAGCUGUUAUCUACUCUUCAGGUUUUGGAGAAACACAAAAUAAGUUAUGAGGAAAAGCAAAUUUCUCUCCUGAGUAUUUACAUGUCUCUGUAUGCUCAAAUAUGCAGAUGUGUCCCUAUGCGUGUAUAUUAGCUUAUUUUUUAGGCUCUAGCCAUUUUAUAUUCUUUCAUGUGCUUCUCAAUAUUCUUUUUCUUUGCACUUUAUACAAAUUAAAAGCAUUUUUAAAGCUUCUUCUGUACUGUAAACUACUAGGUGCUUUGCCAACCAGACAGAUUAGAGGACCUCCGCUACACUGAUGCCUUAUUUGGAACUUAAAAGAGGUGAAAUUCAUAUAUCAUAAAAUUCACCAUUUUAAAGUGUACCAUUCGUUGGCAGAACAUUUACAGUGGUGUGCAACCAUCACUACUCUCUAGUUGCAGAACAUUCUUAUCACCCCCAAAGGAGGCCCUAUACCUAUUAAGCAGUUAGUCCCCAUUCCCUUCUCCUCCGACUGCUAACAAUAGCCACUAAUCUGCACCCUGUCUCUGUGGAUUUACCUAUUCUGGAUAUUUCAUAUAAAUGGAAUCAUAUGAUAUGUGACCUUUUUAUGUAUCUGGCUUCUUUCACUUAGCAUAAUAUUUUCUUUUCUUUUUUUUUUUUUUUUUGAGACAGAGUUUUACUCUUAUUGCCCAGGCUGGAGUGCAAUGGCGCAAUCUCAACCUCCGCCUCCCAGGUUCAAGAGAUUCUCCUGCCUCAGCUUCCCAAGUAGCUGGGAUUACUAGUGUGUACCACCACGCCCAGCUAAUUUUUGUACCUUUAGUAUAGAGACAGGGUUUCACCAUGUUGGCCCAGCUGGUCCUGAGCUGACCUCAGGUGAUCCAACUGCCUCGGCCUCCCAAAGUGCUGGGAUUAUAGGUGUGAGCUACCACACCGGGACAUCAUCAUAUUUUCAAGUUUAACCAACAUUAUAGCAUGUAUCAGUACUUUAUUCCUUUUUAUGGCUAAAUAAUAUUCCAUUGUAUGGAUAUCAUAUUUUGUUUAUCCGGUAUCUGUUGAUGAUUUGGGUUGUUUCCUUCUUUUGGCUAUUGUGAAUAAUGCUUCAGUGAACAUUUGUGUACAAAUAUUUGUUUGAAUACCUGUUUUCAAUUUUUUUGGGUGUACACCUAGGAAUGGAAUUGCUGCGUUUGUUGUUGUGUUGUUGUUGUUGUCGUUGUUUUUUGAGAUGGAGUUUCACUCUGUUGCCCAGGCUGGAGUGCAAUGGCGUGAUCUCGGCUCACCACAACUUCUGCCUCCCAGGUUCAAGCGAUUCUCCUGCCUCAGCCUCCCGAGUAGCUGGGAUUAAGGCAUGCGCCACCACACCUGGCUAAUUUUGUGUUUUUAGUAGAGAUGGGGUUUCUCCAUGUUGGUCAGGCUGGUCUCGAACUCCUGACCUUAGGUGAUCCACCCGCCUCAACCUCCCAGAGUGCUGGGAUGAUUACAGGCAUGAGCCACCAUACCCGGCCUGAGCCACCACACCCAGCCUACGUUUGUUUUUUAAGCCAUAGAAGAUUCUUCCCACCAGUCGGGCACAGUGGCUCACACCUGUAAUCCCAGCACUUCAGGAGGCCAAGGCGGGCGGAUCACAAGAUCAGGAGCUCAAGACCAGCCUGGCCAACACAGUGAAACUCCAUCUCUACAAAAAUUAGCCAGGCAUAGUGGCAGGUGCCUGUAGUCUCAGCUACUUGGGAGACUGAGGCAGGAGAAUCACUUGAACCUGGGAGGCAGAGGUUUCGGUGAGCCGAGAUGGCGCCACUGCACUCCAGCCUGGGCGACAGACUGAGACACGGUCUCAAAAAAAAAAAAAAAAAAAAAAAGAGGAAGAAGAUUCUUCCCUUACCCUGCAAUAGUAGACCAGAAAAAUUAGGAAUAUCUUGAAUUUGAAAGGGACCUAAUGCCUGGCACAGUGGCUCACGCAUGUAAUCUCAGAACUCUGGGAGGCAGAGGUGGGCGGAUCGCCUGAACUCAGGAUUUGAGACCAGCCUGGCCAACAUGGUGAAACCCUGUCUCUAAAAAAAAAAAAAAAAUUAGCCAGGCGUGAUGGCAUGCACUUGUGGUCCCAGCUACUCAGGAAGCUGAGGUCAGAGGAUCACCUGAACCUGGGAAGCAGAGGUUGCAGUGAACUGAGAUCACGCCACUGUACUGGCUGACAAAGUGAGACCCCUGUCUAAAAAAAAGAUAAAGAGAGUUACCUGAAUCUGGAAUCCUUAAUCUUGGUUUUCCUUAAACUUUCUAUAAGUCCAGCAUCUGAAAUAUUUUGUCAAUUAUCACAUUAAUGUGUUCAUUUUGUAAGUAAGAGUACUCAAUUUAAAAUGAUCUUACUUUAAAAGUGGCCUAGUUUGCAGUGCCCAGCAGGACACUGACAGUCACAGCUGUGUGACUUUUUGUGGGUUACUUAAUUUUUUUGAGCCUCCUUUUCUCUUCUAUUCAAUGAGGAUAAUAGGGCCUACCUCAUAGGAUUAUUAUGCAUUCCCCUCUGUUAAUGCACGUAAAGUUUUUACUUGGAAAACUAACUCACCAUUUAACAACCAUUCUAAGCACCAUAGGAUAUAUUUUGUUUCACAAAUUUGGUAUUCAUUCAGAAUAAGUAUUUGAAAAGUGAGUAAAUUCUAUGCAAUUAUAGUUAUUAAAUGACUUAUAAACUGUGUUUCUCUUCCACUUCUUGCUACAUUUAAUCUUCUAGGUGUUCAGAUAUCUUUGGAGAUUAUAGGCAGCAAUAAAGCUAAGGCAGCUAACCUUUCAACAUUCUUGUGUCAGGCUAAUAUUUUGGUGAAAGGAAUUCUUGUGUUUCUCAAAGAACUAGAGCUGAAGCAGAAAUAAGUUCCAAUGAGCAAGUGUCCAAUCGGACCAUUGAAUGAAAUCUAGUGUUUUAAACAAUUCUGAUGUUUCAAUGUUUUGUUCUGUUUUCUUUUGAUCUUGUGAGCAGUAAGACAUAUUUUAUGUGGGUGGUAAAGGAAGAAAUCAAGUAACAGAAUGAGGAAUUGUUCCCAGGAAGAGUUAGAGUUGGGACAAAUGGGUUGUUAACUUUGAUUUUUAGAUCUUCUCUGAAGACAUUAAACAUGGAAUGGUCAUCUUUAGAAAAAUAAAAGACUAUGCAACUCCACCACUGAAAUGGUAUCUUAUUACAGUGAAUGAUGGAUAAUCUGAAAUUACUAUAGAAAAAAAUAAACCCAGACCAUUUUGCCUAGAGCCUUUCAACCACC